ACAACCCCAUGACAAGAAGGACCCAGCCUCCGAGCGGCCACACCCUGUGUGUCUCUCUGUCCUGCCAGCACUGAGGGCUCAUCCCUCUGCAGAGCGCGGGGUCACCGGGAGGAGACGCCAUGACGCCCGCCCUCACAGCCCUGCUCUGCCUUGGGCUGAGUCUGGGCCCCAGGACCCGCGUGCAGGCAGGGCCCUUCCCCAAACCCACCCUCUGGGCUGAGCCAGGCUCUGUGAUCAGCUGGGGGAGCCCCGUGACCAUCUGGUGUCAGGGGAGCCUGGAGGCCCAGGAGUACCGACUGGAUAAAGAGGGAAGCCCAGAGCCCUUGGACAGAAAUAACCCACUGGAACCCAAGAACAAGGCCAGAUUCUCCAUCCCAUCCAUGACAGAGCACCAUGCGGGGAGAUACCGCUGCCACUAUUACAGCUCUGCAGGCUGGUCAGAGCCCAGCGACCCCCUGGAGCUGGUGAUGACAGGAUUCUACAACAAACCCACCCUCUCAGCCCUGCCCAGCCCUGUGGUGGCCUCAGGGGGGAAUAUGACCCUCCGAUGUGGCUCACAGAAGGGAUAUCACCAUUUUGUUCUGAUGAAGGAAGGAGAACACCAGCUCCCCCGGACCCUGGACUCACAGCAGCUCCACAGUGGGGGGUUCCAGGCCCUGUUCCCUGUGGGCCCCGUGAACCCCAGCCACAGGUGGAGGUUCACAUGCUAUUACUAUUAUAUGAACACCCCCCAGGUGUGGUCCCACCCCAGUGACCCCCUGGAGAUUCUGCCCUCAGGCGUGUCUAGGAAGCCCUCCCUCCUGACCCUGCAGGGCCCUGUCCUGGCCCCUGGGCAGAGCCUGACCCUCCAGUGUGGCUCUGAUGUCGGCUACGACAGAUUUGUUCUGUAUAAGGAGGGGGAACGUGACUUCCUCCAGCGCCCUGGCCAGCAGCCCCAGGCUGGGCUCUCCCAGGCCAACUUCACCCUGGGCCCUGUGAGCCCCUCCCACGGGGGCCAGUACAGGUGCUAUGGUGCACACAACCUCUCCUCCGAGUGGUCGGCCCCCAGCGACCCCCUGAACAUCCUGAUGGCAGGACAGAUCUAUGACACCGUCUCCCUGUCAGCACAGCCGGGCCCCACAGUGGCCUCAGGAGAGAACGUGACCCUGCUGUGUCAGUCAUGGUGGCAGUUUGACACUUUCCUUCUGACCAAAGAAGGGGCAGCCCAUCCCCCACUGCGUCUGAGAUCAAUGUACGGAGCUCAUAAGUACCAGGCUGAAUUCCCCAUGAGUCCUGUGACCUCAGCCCACGCGGGGACCUACAGGUGCUACGGCUCAUACAGCUCCAACCCCCACCUGCUGUCUUUCCCCAGUGAGCCCCUGGAACUCAUGGUCUCAGGACACUCUGGAGGCUCCAGCCUCCCACCCACAGGGCCGCCCUCCACACCUGGUCUGGGAAGAUACCUGGAGGUUUUGAUUGGGGUCUCGGUGGCCUUCGUCCUGCUGCUCUUCCUCCUCCUCUUCCUCCUCCUCCGACGUCAGCGUCACAGCAAACACAGGACAUCUGACCAGAGAAAGACUGAUUUCCAGCGUCCUGCAGGGGCUGCGGAGACAGAGCCCAAGGACAGGGGCCUGCUGAGGAGGUCCAGCCCAGCUGCUGACGUCCAGGAAGAAAACCUCUAUGCUGCCGUGAAGGACACACAGUCUGAGGACAGGGUGGAGCUGGACAGUCAGAGCCCACACGAUGAAGACCCCCAGGCAGUGACGUAUGCCCCGGUGAAACACUCCAGUCCUAGGAGAGAAAUGGCCUCUCCUCCCUCCUCACUGUCUGGGGAAUUCCUGGACACAAAGGACAGACAGGUGGAAGAGGACAGGCAGAUGGACACUGAGGCUGCUGCAUCUGAAGCCUCCCAGGAUGUGACCUACGCCCAGCUGCACAGCUUGACCCUUAGACGGAAGGCAACUGAGCCUCCUCCAUCCCAGGAAGGGGAACCUCCAGCUGAGCCCAGCAUCUACGCCACUCUGGCCAUCCACUAGCCCGGGGGGUACGCAGACCCCACACUCAGCAGAAGGAGACUCAGGACUGCUGAAGGCACGGGAGCUGCCCCCAGUGGACACCAGUGAACCCCAGUCAGCCUGGACCCCUAACACAGACCAUGAGGAGACGCUGGGAACUUGUGGGACUCACCUGACUCAAAGAUGACUAAUAUCGUCCCAUUUUGGAAAUAAAGCAACAGACUUCUCAACAAUCAAUGAGUUAAUAACAAAAAAACAAAAAACAAAAACAGACGUAAAGGCCGGGUGUGGUACUCAGGAGGCUGAGUGGGGAGGAUUCCUUGAACACAAGAAGUUAAGGCUGCUGAGGCUGCAGUGAGCUAUGACUGUGCCACUGCACUCCAGCCUGUGUGACAGAGCGAGACCUUGUCUCUAAAAAAAAAAACAGUGAAUGUUUUAAACUGAAUGAUAAUGUAAAUAUUAUACAUCGAACUUAUGACAUGGGAAAAUUAAGAAGCAUAAAUAGGCCGGGCGCGGUGGCUCACGCCUAUAAUCUCAGCACUUUGGGAGGCUGAUGCGGGCGGAUCAUGAGGUCAGGAGAUCGAGACCAUCCUGGCUAACACGGUGAAACCCCGUCUCUACUAAAAAUACAAAAAAAUUAGCCGGGCGUGGUGGCGAGUGCCUAUAGUCCCAGCUACUCAGGAGGCUGAGGCAGGAGAAUGGCAUGAGCCCGGGAGGCAGAGCUUGCAGUGAGCUGAGAUCGCACCACUGCACUCCAGCCUGGGCGACAGAGUGAGAUUCCGUCUCGAAAAAAAAAAAAAAAGAAAGAAAAAAAAUAAAAAAGAAGCAUAACCAGG